GCUGAGCUGAGCUCGGUCGCGGCUGCCUGUCUGCUCCGGCAGCACCAUGUCGCUCUUGGUCGUCAGCAUGGCGUGUGUUGGGUUCUUCUUGCUGCAGGGGGCCUGGCCACAUGAGGGAGUCCACAGAAAACCUUCCCUCCUGGCCCACCCAGGUCCCCUGGUGAAAUCAGAAGAGACAGUCAUCCUGCAAUGUUGGUCAGAUGUCAUGUUUGAACACUUCCUUCUGCACAGAGAGGGGAUGUUUAACGACACUUUGCGCCUCAUUGGAGAACACCAUGAUGGGGUCUCCAAGGCCAACUUCUCCAUCAGUCGCAUGACGCAAGACCUGGCAGGGACCUACAGAUGCUACGGUUCUGUUACUCACUCCCCCUAUCAGGUGUCAGCUCCCAGUGACCCUCUGGACAUCGUGAUCAUAGGUCUAUAUGAGAAACCUUCUCUCUCAGCCCAGCCGGGCCCCACGGUUCUGGCAGGAGAGAAUGUGACCUUGUCCUGCAGCUCCCGGAGCUCCUAUGACAUGUACCAUCUAUCCAGGGAAGGGGAGGCCCAUGAACGUAGGCUCCCUGCAGGGCCCAAGGUCAACGGAACAUUCCAGGCUGACUUUCCUCUGGGCCCUGCCACCCACGGAGGGACCUACAGAUGCUUCGGCUCUUUCCAUGACUCUCCAUACGAGUGGUCAAAGUCAAGUGACCCACUGCUUGUUUCUGUCACAGGAAACCCUUCAAAUAGUUGGCCUUCACCCACUGAACCAAGCUCCAAAACCGGUGAGUACAGAACCCUCUUAUAUCCGCUUUUGGAACCCUGGGGAGGUGGGAACCUUGGAUUCAGGCGUUGA